GAAAACAUAAGGGAAAAGCUCCACGACAUUGGUCUGGGCAAUGAUUUUUUUGGAUAUGACCUCAAAAGGACAGGCAGCAAACGCAAAAAUAGAAAAAUAGUAUCACAGUGAACUAAAAAGCUUCUGUACAGCAAAGGAAACAGUAACAGAGUGAAGACAGACAACGGAGUGGGAGAAAAUAUUUGCACGCUAUGCAAGUGAUUAUGAAGAGGCAUCUUCUGGGGUAAAUACCCAGGGUUCGUCGUCUUGCACCAGGAGGAAUAAGGACAUGGACACAUGUGGGUGGGUUAAGGAGUGCAAGGCUUAAUAGGUAGAAGAAAGGAGAGAGGAGAGCAGCUCUGUGUGACAGGAAACAGGCCUCCGAAAAGGAAAAGUAGGCCUGUAGCAGACAGCAGGCAAUUUUACAGGCAGGCUUGAGGAGGCGGUGUCUGAUUUAUGUAGGGCCCAGAUUGGCUAGACCAGGUGUGACGUCUACAUGAUGCCAGGCGAAGGCUGGUUGCCCUACCCUGAUCUUAUUAUGCAAAUAGACUUUCCACUUGUCCGCCAUCUUGUCCGCUCCUUACUGCACAAGUGGCUGGCAAAGAGAAGAUGGAGCCGCCAUUUUGAACAUGCCUAUUCCUUAGUGACGUCUCAGUAUGUUGCCCAGGCUGAUCUCAAACUCCCAGAUUUAAGCAAUUCACUGGUCUCAGCUUCCCAAAGUGUUGGGGUUACAGAUCCACAUCUUCAUUUGAAUAUUGAGGAAUCAAACCAAGAGUUUAUGGUGAAAAGUGAAGAACUCUACGACUCCCUCAUGAAUUGCCACUGGCAGCCUCUGGACACAGUUCACUCCGAAAUCCCAGAUGAGACCCCGAAGUGAAGCAAGGUGUUCAUUAAACUCCGCAAUUAUCAUA